GUUCACUGUCUCAGUGAGUCUCUUGGCAGUAGGGCCCCGUCCCUGUCCGCCACCGCACAGUGACAUACUUUCUCCCGCCCUCUCCCCUAGGUCAGCUGGAACUGGGUCCGCCUGGAAACCCGGGGGCCGGGCCCCCAGAGGGCUUUCGCAGCCUGGCCGCCCGAAGCUCACCUGCCCUUUCACUGAACUCCACCCGGAAGGUGCCCGGGGCUUCGUGUUCCUGGGUGCUGACCGUGCACUCCCCGCCGCCCGAGGACUUAGAGCUCUGGAAGUAGCUCUCCAGCUUCCUUCGUACUCGGGGGCCGGACUUGUACACCCGCACGAGGAGCGGGGACGGCGGGCGCAGAAGUGGGCCACCAUAUCUGGAAACUACAGUCUAUGCUUUGAAGCGCAAAAGGGAAUAAACAUUUAAAGACUCCCCCGGGGACCUGGAGGAUGGACUUUUCCAUGGUGGCCGGAGCAGCAGCUUACAAUGAAAAAUCAGAGACUGGUGCUCUUGGAGAAAACUAUAGUUGGCAAAUUCCCAUUAACCACAAUGACUUCAAAAUUUUAAAAAAUAAUGAGCGUCAGCUGUGUGAAGUCCUCCAGAAUAAGUUUGGCUGUAUCUCUACCCUGGUCUCUCCAGUUCAGGAAGGCAACAGCAAAUCUCUGCAAGUGUUCAGAAAAAUGCUGACUCCUAGGAUAGAGUUAUCAGUCUGGAAAGAUGACCUCACCACACAUGCUGUUGAUGCUGUGGUGAAUGCAGCCAAUGAAGAUCUUCUGCAUGGGGGAGGCCUGGCCCUGGCCCUGGUAAAAGCUGGUGGAUUUGAAAUCCAAGAAGAGAGCAAACAGUUUGUUGCCAGAUAUGGUAAAGUGUCAGCUGGUGAGAUAGCUGUCACGGGAGCAGGGAGGCUUCCCUGCAAACAGAUCAUCCAUGCUGUUGGGCCUCGGUGGAUGGAAUGGGAUAAACAGGGAUGUACUGGAAAGCUGCAGAGGGCCAUUGUAAGUAUUCUGAAUUAUGUCAUCUAUAAAAAUACUCACAUUAAGACAGUAGCAAUUCCAGCCUUGAGCUCUGGGAUUUUUCAGUUCCCUCUGAAUUUGUGUACAAAGACUAUUGUAGAGACUAUCCGGGUUAGUUUGCAAGGGAAGCCAAUGAUGAGUAAUUUGAAAGAAAUUCACCUGGUGAGCAAUGAGGACCCUACUGUUGCUGCCUUUAAAGCUGCUUCAGAAUUCAUCCUAGGGAAGAGUGAGCUGGGACAAGAAACCACCCCUUCUUUCAAUGCAAUGGUCGUGAACAACCUGACCCUCCAGAUUGUCCAGGGCCACAUUGAAUGGCAGACGGCAGAUGUAAUUGUUAAUUCUGUAAACCCACAUGAUAUUACAGUUGGACCUGUGGCAAAGUCAAUUCUACAACAAGCAGGAGUUGAAAUGAAAUCGGAAUUUCUUGCCACAAAGGCUAAACAGUUUCAACGGUCCCAGUUGGUACUGGUCACAAAAGGAUUUAACUUGUUCUGUAAAUAUAUAUACCAUGUACUGUGGCAUUCAGAAUUUCCUAAACCUCAGAUAUUAAAACAUGCAAUGAAGGAGUGUUUGGAAAAAUGCAUUGAGCAAAAUAUAACUUCCAUUUCCUUUCCUGCCCUUGGGACUGGAAACAUGGAAAUAAAGAAGGAAACAGCAGCAGAGAUUUUGUUUGAUGAAGUUUUAACAUUUGCCAAAGACCAUGUAAAACACCAGUUAACUGUAAAAUUUGUGAUCUUUCCAACAGAUUUGGAGAUAUAUAAGGCUUUCAGUUCUGAAAUGGCAAAGAGGUCCAAGAUGCUGAGUUUGAACAAUUACAGUGUCCCCCAGUCAACCAGAGAGGAGAAAAGAGAAAAUGGGCUUGAAGCUAGAUCUCCUGCCAUCAAUCUGAUGGGAUUCAACGUGGAAGAGAUGUAUGAGGCCCACGCAUGGAUCCAAAGAAUCCUGAGUCUCCAGAACCACCACAUCAUUGAGAAUAAUCAUAUUCUGUACCUUGGGAGAAAGGAACAUGACAUUUUGUCUCAGCUUCAGAAAACUUCAAGUGUCUCCAUCACAGAAAUUAUCAGCCCAGGAAGGACAGAGUUAGAGAUUGAAGGAGCCCGGGCUGACCUCAUUGAGGUGGUUAUGAACAUUGAAGAUAUGCUUUGUAAAGUACAGGAGGAAAUGGCAAGGAAAAAGGAGCGAGGCCUUUGGCGCUCGUUAGGACAGUGGACUAUUCAGCAACAAAAAACCCAAGACGAAAUGAAAGAAAAUAUCAUAUUUCUGAAAUGUCCUGUGCCUCCAACUCAAGAGCUUCUAGAUCAAAAGAAACAGUUUGAAAAAUGUGGUUUGCAGGUUCUAAAGGUGGAGAAGAUAGACAAUGAGGUCCUUAUGGCUGCCUUUCAAAGAAAGAAGAAAAUGAUGGAAGAAAAACUGCACAGGCAACCUGUGAGCCAUAGGCUGUUUCAGCAAGUCCCAUACCAGUUCUGCAAUGUGGUAUGCAGAGUUGGCUUUCAAAGAAUGUACUCGACACCUUGCGGUAGGUGUCAAUGCCUCAUCAUUGGGGCUACUCUGUGGAAUUUGGUGAGCUGACAUCAGUAGAUUCUUCCACUGAUAGCAUUUGUUGUUGUGGGGAAGGGAUCAUUUGUGACUGUGAUUUAGAGGUCACAAAUGAUGACCCAGGUCACAAAGUAUUUUGGAAAGAGUGGUAUUUUUUACUUUUCCUUCGUAUCUUUUGUUGCUGAUGCAUUUUACAUUGAUGAAAAGUGUGAGCAGUAAGAACUACGGUUCACUGUUUUUCUCCUUUAUGUGUUUCUGUGUCCUAUCCGCAGAGAACACGUUGAGGCUUUUUUUUUUUUUUUUUGCCUUACUUAUCUCAACAAAAUUAUUACCAACAGCACUGAACCGUCCUCAUCCCUUAAUUAAAAGGGCAUUUUCCCAAAUUUAAGAAAGUUGGUCUUUUCUCUUUCAUCCCUUUGUUUCCUAUAGCCUGCUAGUGAAUGAAUUAGGUAUCAUUUGGCAGGUGAAGUGCAUAACAUCUUAAGAUCCUCUUCAUCCAUAGGAGUUCUAUGUGUAACUCCCAUGUCUCUUUUCAGAUGUACAAAAACAUUGCAUAUAUAAUUCUUAUAUUGCCCCCUCUACUCCUCAGUCACUAAUGAAGAUUUCUGGCUUUAGUUCUCUCCAAAAGAGGAAAAGAAAUUUAGUAAAAAUUAUGGAGAGAUACUUAGCGGGGUGGCUUGAUUUUGCUUGGUCUAUUAAAUAUGUGGCUCUUGAUCUUUAUCUUUCAACAUAUGUAGCAUGAUCCUUGCUGAGGAGUCAAUUCCAAUAGACUUGGUUUCUAGGAUGCAAAGGCUCUAGAAAUCAUCUUUUCUUUGUUCUGGAGAGAACAUAGGCAAAACUUGGGGUAAAUGUUGAACAUAGACAAUUACUGGGGAUAAAAAUAGAGAAAUGAAUCCCUACCAAGAAGCCUUUUGGGGCAAUCAGGAAAGUGAUGAUCAGUAUAGUCCCUUCAUUAGCAAAGUCUUAAAAAAUCUAUAAUUUCCAUUUGCUCCUAAAGCUGGCUUCUCUGCAAUCCCCACCCACUACUUCUACUUAAAUUACUUUCAUUAAGAUCAUCGCUGUGCUCUUACUUUCCAAAUCUAGUGAGUAUUCUCUUUUCAGUCCUGUGACAGACUCUGCUACUUGCCUACCCAACAUCUAUACACAUCUUUCUUACUAAAACAUCUAAGACACCCACUAUCCUCCCAAGGAAUAUGGUCCCAAGGUCUUAGCCAGACUCAUCAUCAGCUCAAGUUCAGGCAGUUCUCUCUUUAUUUAUUUAUUUAUUUUUCUGAGACGGAGUCUUGCUCUGUCACUCAGGCUGGAGUGCAGUGGCACCAUCUUGGCUCACUGCAACCUCCGCCUCCGAGAUUCAAACAGUUCUCCUGCCUCAGCCUCCCAGGUAGCUGGGAUUACAGGCAUGUGCCACCACGUGCAGUUAAUUUUUGUAUUUUUUUUAGUAGAGACGAGGUUUCAUCAUGUUGGCCAGGCUGAUCUCCAGCUACUCGUGAUCCGUCCACCUCAGCCUCCCAAAGUGUUGGGCUUACAGGUAUGAGCCACCAUGCCCAGCAGGCAGUUCUCUCUUAAAGCUUAAAGGCAAGAUACUGCCCCCAACAUACUCAUUAUAUAGUGAUAUAAAAAGGAGCGGGAAAACUGCAAUGAAAACUCUCAUGUUGAAAGGGGAGAAGCAAAACACACAACAGCCACUGGCUCACACCACUUAUCUACAUGCUGCCGAACAGGUAUAGAGAGGACUCCCUAUUCCAUGUUGUAAAACCUUUAUUUUGCACUCUGGGAAAAUCUUCCUUAUAUAUUGUGGCCCUUGGCUAUUUCCAGGUUCAUUGCCUAUCAGGGAGCCAUGGAUUUUCUCACAGGCUAGAAUGUGCUCAGGCUGUUGCAACCAGGCUUGUGGUUUCUUCAGCAAUACAGUUCCUUUAAAAAUUCAGUGGGCACGAGGCCUAAUUUCUUCUGGUUAAGUUUAUGUCUUUAUAACCUAACCACAGAUCUUGUCUCCAUAUAGUCUUUCAACUCAAGAUUUUGGUCUCUUACCUGCUGUCUGUGUGCUCUGCCCUUCUCCCUAUCCCUUAGCUUAACAGCCACUGCCUUGAGGCAAUUCAGACAUGACUCAUAAUGUGACCUGCACCAAUUGACUCAUCUCUGUAGGCUAGAGAGAACUCUUAACAGAAGGUGCCAGACAAGCCCAGGAGACACCAAUCUUGCUACCACUGAAGCUGUUGUUAUUUGGAGUACAAAAGCUCUUAGCUUUUUCAGCCGUGCAAUAUUCCAAAUUAUAGGACUCUCAGUCAAUUUAGAUGGCCACCCACAGGCAAAGGAGACAGAACUUCUGUUAACAAACCUUUAUUUUCUUUUUUCUAUUUAUGUUUGCAUUCCAACCAGUUCUGAAUAAAUCUCUUGCUUGUAGGACUUGGUUGAGUGCAGCAAGAAGGCAUCUACACAUGCAGUUUCUUACUGGGUUGAUUCAUUUGUUCCACAGGUAUUUAUUAAGCACAUUCUAUGAAUCAGGCCCUGUGCUAGGGGUACUAGAAAUAGAGUGUAAAUAAAAAACCAUAGAGUUCUUGCCCUUACAAUUUAUAAUCUCACGAGUUCACCUGUUGCCCAUUCUUUAUCUUCUCUCUUUUUUCCUCUACGAUGUCCCCCUUGGUGAUGGCACCUGUUCCCAUGGCCUCAACUCCUACCUCAAUGAUGACGACUUAGGAAUUUCUAACUCUUAACUCCCUACCUCUCUCCUGACCUGCAGGUUCAUAUGUCUCACUCUCUUUUUGACAUCUUUACCCAGAUGUCCCAUAGGUAACUCAAAUUGAUCCCUUUUCUUGGUCAUGAUUUUCCCUAAGAAAUAUGCCCUUUGUUUGCUGAUUCUCCCUAACCUGGUUAGUAUCAUCACCAUCUACCUACCAGGUUUCCUAAGGCUGAAACAUUAUCAUCCUCCAUUCCUCCUUUUCCCUCACCCUUAUACCCAGGCAUUCACCCAGUCCUAGUGAUUCACUCUCAUGAAGAUCUCAGCCCAGUUUCACCUCUCUAUUCCUACUGCCUUAGUUAAUCUUCCUUCAGACCUAGACUAUUACUAGGUCCUCUCCUUGCCACAAAACACACCCCUACCUAAUCUAUCCUUUACCACCAGAAUUAUCACGCUAAAAAUUACAUUCUUGCUUAAUAUCUGUAUUCCCAGUUGCCUACGGGAUAAAAGCCCAAACUCCUUAGCAGAGAAUAUAAGGCCCUAGCUCCCACAUUAUUUCAGCAGUCAUCACCCACUAUGUUCCUCAAGACUGCAGCCAUUAACUUUUUAGAGUUCCCUAAACAUGCUGUUUACUUUCAUGCCUCUAUCCCGUUGUCUGUGGAAUGACUUCCCUCCUUGCCCUUUUCAGUGCUACAAACCCCUAUUCUUUAAGACAUAGUACAAAUGGCAUCUCCUGGUUGGCAUCUUUCCUGCAGGCCUACAGGCCUAGUAAGUAUCUUCCUCCUCUGUGCUCCUGCAUACCUCCAUUCCUUUGUUAUGACAUCUAUAACUUUAAUAAGUACUAAAAUCUGUAGUCCUACAAAACUCAGGCAUAGAACUCAUUUCCUUUAUGGCUCUAUAAUGGAACUUUACCCAACUCUCACGUUCCCCAUGACCACAGAUGUGGAAAAUUUGAAUCUUGACAGUUCAAGGUGAACUCAGUCAUUUUCAGAGUUUUCAUAGUCCCUUCAAGAUUGAAACUCAGUUCCUGCAAUGUUUGCCCCUUUUCUCCUCUUUUGUCUAUGCUGGGAGAGGCAUUGUGGGGAGGGUUGUCUGGCUUAUGGCUCCCAUUGUCCUCUGCUUGAUAAACCACCUGAGCUUUGGUCAUUAGCAGUCUCCUGUGCCUUUCACACUCAGGUAGUGUCUGCACAGGCCACUCUAUGUCUUUUCCAUGCUGAAGAAAUUCCUUUCCAGGCCAUGUCUGUGUUCCUCCUGCCACACAGGAAAUUUUUGAGCAUGUUCAUCCUCCAAGCUGAAUGCAGGGUCUUGGGUAGUGGUCCUCACCUGCUCCAGAGACUUCUCCAGCCAUUGCCACUCUCCACUCAGGUGAUGAAGCUGGAUGAGGGACUGCACCCACCAGAGUCAGGCCAGGGUCCUGUCUGCUCUGUGAGUCCCUCCAAUUGUUCUUAUUCCGAGAUUUCCAUUGUUCUGCCCCCUCUUGACUCCCAGGGCUCUCAAGGGAGUGGGGGUAGUGAAGGGAGCCCUUUCCCAAGCUCCCCCAAGAGCUCUAGUCACAUCACUUCUGAUACUUCUUUUCCCACCAGCUGGAAGAAAGAACUUUCAUUUGUCUUGAAAUGAGAAAAAUGUUCUUAGAAUAUUUUGUAUUACUCUCUGCUCUGUCAUUUAUGGUAAACAAAAUAAAAUAAUAAAAAAAAACAACCCA